ACUCUUGCCUGUAUCGCAUGGCACUGAGGUUGCUGUCUUCUUUUCUUGCUCCUUCGCCUGCAAAGCCAAAGGCCAAAGCAAGGACUGCGUCUUGCUGAUGAUUCGGUCCUCAGCAGCCAGCACCUUCGCCGGCACGGGCGAUGCCCUCCUAGCUAGCCGUCACGGGAUGGAGGGCUUCAUGGACUCAGGGACACAGACGGACGCCGUGGUGGUGCUGUCCUUGGCUCAGGCCGCCGUGCUUGGCCUGGUCUCCGAAAAUGAGCUCUUUGGAGCUACCAUAAGCGCCGAGGCCUUCUACCCGGACCUGGGGCCCGAGCUUUCAGGGGCAGCCAUGGGAGAGCCCGAGCCACCAGGCCCCGACGUCUACCAGCUGGCCUGCAACGGGAGGGCCUUGGAGGAGCCGGCGGAGGAGGAGGUGCUGGAGGUGGAGGCAGCCUGUGAGAAGCACACCCGGCGGAAGACGCGGCCACCUGUGCGGUUGGUGCCCAAGGUCAAGUUCGAGAAGGUGGAGGAGGAGGAACAGGAGGUCUAUGAGGUUUCUGUGCCAGGUGACGACAAGGACGCAGGGCCAGCAGAAGCCCCCGCCGAGGCGGCCAGUGGCGGCUGCGACGCCCUGGUGCAGAGCAGCGCCGUCAAGAUGAUCGACCUCAGCGCCUUCAGCCGCAAGCCCCGGACGCUCCGGCAUCUGCCCCGAACCCCGAGGCCGGAGCUGAACGUGGCCCCAUAUGACCCUCACUUCCCGGCCCCGGCCCGGGAUGGCUUCCCCGAGCCCAGCAUGGCGCUGCCUGGGCCAGAGGCCUUGCCCACAGAGUGUGGGUUCGAGCCACCCCACCUGGCCCCCCUGAGUGACCCCGAGGCCCCCAGCAUGGAGUCCCCGGAGCCUGUCAAGCCGGAACAGGGCUUCGUGUGGCAGGAGGCCAGUGAGUUCGAGGCUGACACGGCGGGUUCGACCGUGGAACGCCACAAGAAGGCCCAGCUGGAUCGGCUGGACAUCAACGUGCAGAUUGACGACUCCUAUCUGGUGGAGGCGGGCGACCGCCAGAAGCGCUGGCAGUGCCGCAUGUGCGAGAAGUCCUACACGUCCAAGUACAACCUGGUGACGCACAUCCUGGGCCACAACGGCAUCAAGCCACACUCGUGCCCACACUGCAGCAAGCUCUUCAAGCAGCCCAGCCACCUGCAGACGCACCUGCUGACGCACCAGGGCACCCGGCCCCACAAGUGCCAGGUAUGCCACAAGGCCUUCACGCAGACCAGCCACCUCAAGCGCCACAUGCUGCUGCACUCGGAGGUCAAGCCCUACAGCUGCCACUUCUGCGGCCGCGGCUUCGCCUACCCCAGCGAGCUCAAGGCCCACGAAGUGAAGCAUGAGAGUGGCCGCUGCCAUGUCUGCGUCGAGUGCGGCCUGGACUUCUCCACCCUGACCCAGCUCAAGCGCCACCUGGCCUCCCACCAGGGCCCCACCCUCUACCAGUGCCUCGAGUGUGACAAGUCCUUCCACUACCGCAGCCAGUUGCAGAACCACAUGCUCAAGCACCAGAACGUGCGACCCUUCGUGUGCACUGAAUGCGGCAUGGAGUUCAGCCAGAUUCACCACCUCAAGCAGCACUCCCUCACCCACAAGGGCGUGAAGGAGUUCAAGUGCGAGGUGUGUGGCCGGGAGUUCACCCUACAGGCGAACAUGAAGCGGCACAUGCUGAUCCACACCAGCGUCCGGCCCUACCAGUGCCACAUCUGCUUCAAGACCUUUGUACAGAAGCAGACUCUCAAGACCCACAUGAUUGUACACUCGCCCGUGAAGCCAUUCAAAUGCAAGGUGUGCGGGAAGUCCUUCAACCGCAUGUACAACCUGCUGGGCCACAUGCACCUGCACGCCGGCAGCAAGCCCUUCAAGUGCCCCUACUGCUCCAGCAAGUUUAAUCUCAAGGGCAACCUGAGCCGGCACAUGAAGGUCAAGCAUGGCGUCAUGGACAUCGGCCUGGACAGCCAAGAUGCAGAAACUGAAGAACAGAGAACUUAGAUAGCUCAUGCAAGAUGACAACACAGCAGGAGGUGACAGACACUUUAUUUCGUUACCGUGAGAUAAUAUUUCAAAUAAGUGUAUGGGAAAGAAAGUUAGAAAGGGGAAAAAAUGGCAGCCGGAAAGAUAAGGGAGAGCCAGGUGAGGUCCCAACUCCAAGUACACCAUGGGAGGUCCUAAGCAAGGGACAUGCAGAGGGGAGAUCUGAGCUUCCCAGCAACCAAGGCAAAAAAGUGUCAAUCAGUCACACUCUUCACAAGUGCCUGCCAGAGACUAUAACCCACAUACUCAUGAAAGGGCCAGACAGCCCUGACGUUAAGAUCUGGGAGAAAUUUUAGGAGAGGAUCCUAUGCCUCAGCAGUUCGUAGAAGUUUCAGAGGCUGUCAGAAAACAUCCCAAGUGUUAGCGGUAGCCUUUCCCUCCAGCAGUGGUCAGUACUUAAAGCAUUUCUGUUGGGUGACAGCAAAGCUGUUAGCCUCUCUGGCCUCAUGGUGGGGAGGGACUGCUGUGGAGACUCCACAGGAAGGAGGGAGCCAACAGCGCUACAGGGAGGCUCCUUCUACAGUUGGGAGCUAUUUCUGGUGCUCUGGCUGGGCAUGAUGGCUCACACCUAUAAUCCUGGCACUUUGGGAGGCCGAGGCAGGAGGAUCCCUUAAGGCCAGGAGUUUGAUACCAAACCAGGCAACAUAGUGAGACCUGGUCUCUACAAAAAUAUUUUUAAAUUAGCUGGGUGUGGUGGCGUGUGCCUAUAAUCUCAGCUACUUGGGAGUCUAAGGCAGGAAGAUCACUUGAGCCCAGGAGUUCAAGGCUGUAGUGAACUGUGAUCGGACCACGGCACUCCAGCCUGCGUGGCAAAGCAAGACCCUAUCGCCAAAUUAUAAUAAAGAAAUUCUGGUGUGCCUCUGAGUCACACCAGCUGGGAACAUGCUUUGGCAGUAACCAGGUGAGCUGACUUGCCACGUGGGAUUAUUUACUGGAAUGCAGGCAGGCACGCGGGAACAGCUGCAGUAGCUUAACUCUGGUUUUGGAACAGCUGACCAGUGAAUGGCCUGGGUUUUCUGGCAGAAACAGGUAUCUCAGUUGUUUUGUUUUGUUUUUCAGUUGUCUAUUAAGGUUGCUUCCAGUAGACGAGAAUGAAACCCCGUCGGCUGCUCUUGGUAGCUCCUUGCUACUCAAAAUGUGGUAGGAGGAUGAGCAGCCUCGGCCCCACCUGGGAUCUUGCUGGCCUCUCAGCUCCACCCACACCUGCUGAGUCAGACUCUACACUUCAAAAAGAUCUCUGGGCCAUUUGUUGCAGUCAAGUUUGAGACCCACUGGACCAGACUAGUGCCUCAGAGUCUCCUGGAGGGCUUGUUGAAACAAAGUGCUGGCCCCACCCCCAGAGUUUCUGAUUCAGUAGAUCUGGGGUGGGGUCUGAGACGCUGCCUUUCCCACAAGUUCCCAGUUCUUAGCAAAGCAGCCGCUGGUUCAGGGACCUCAUGUUGAGAACCUUUGAUCCAGACUGCAGAGGGCUGGCUGGCAAAUCAGCUGCAUGUUGGGAGUCACCUGAGGAAUGUUUUAAAUGCUGAUGCCUGAGUUUGGACCUGAGGUUCAAAUGUAAGUGAUCUGGAAUGUGGCCUGGGAUCAGGAUUUUUGUAAAGCACUUUGGGUGAGUCCAUGUGCAGUAGAUUUUGAGAGCUGUAUUCUAGUGGAUCUGCCCUGUUGCUAACCCACCAGAAGGAACCAGAGCAGAACGUGCCCUUUUGGAAAUAACUGGGACCAUGAAGAGACUGUCAGUGUUACAGCUCUUUUAGAAUUUGUUAGGCUGGGCGUACUGGCUCACGCCUAUAAUCCCAACACUUUGGGAGGCAAAUCCCAAGGUGGGCAGAUCACCUGAGGUUGGGAGUUCGAGACCAGCCUGGCUAACAUGAUGAAACCCCGUCUCUACUAAAAAUACAAAAAUUAGCUGGGCGUGUUGGCACAUGCGUGUAAUCCCAGCUACUCGGGAGGCUGAGGCAGGAGAAUCACUUGAACCUGGGAGGCAGAGGUUGCAGUGAGCCGAGAUUGUGUCACUGCACUCCAGCCUGGGUGACAGAGUGAGACUUUGACUCAAAAAAAAAAAAAAAAAAGCAUUCAUUUAGCAGGUUUUCCAGUUUUUACCAGAAAUCGCCCCACCCCCAUCCCACCACCCAAACAAGAUUUUUUAAAAAGACUGUCCCUGUACACCUUGUUCCUCGGGGUGGUUAAGGCACAACCUCUUUCUAUAUGAGCUCAGUCACCAGGGAUGCUUAGAAUUCCUCUAUUCCUGGCCGUACCAGAUGACAGAAGGAAGCGAUUGGCCCUGGAAUGACUGGGCUCCAGGUCCCCACCUCCCUCAUACAGCCUUGGUCUGGGAAGCCCAGGCUUGAUGCGUAUGCAGAAGGAAGGCAGCAUACAUUCUAGACAGAACGAUCUAGUAACUAUGGGGCUGUCAUUUGGGGAGGUGGAUCAAUGUCCUUAUAAAAAAUGCUACAGACUAUUCUCUGGGGCCCACAGGACGGGACCAUAGACUUAAUAAACAAAAUGGGGACGGUGUACAGAGAUCCACAAGUAGAAAUUUUCUCAAGGUGCUUUUUUUUUUUUUUUUUUUUUUGAGACGGAGUCUUGCUCUUUCACCCAGGCUGGAGUGCAGUGGCGCGAUCUCGGCUCACUGCAAGCUCCACCUCCUGGGUUCACGCCAUUCUCCUGCCUCAGCCUCCCAAGUAGCUGGGACUACAGGCGCCUGCCACCACGCCCGGCUAAUUUUUUUGUAUUUUUAGUAGAGACGGGGUUUCACGGUGUUAGCCAGGAUGGUCUUGAUCUCCUGACCUCAUGAUCUGCCUGCCUUGGCCUCCCAAAGUGCUGGGAUUACAGGCAUGAGCCACUGCGCCUGGCCCCCAAGGUGCUUUAUUUAGCUUGUUUUUGAAACCAGCUGUGUAACAUGAGGGUGUGGCACUAGGACUGAGGGAAGAAACAGCCCAAAUCUAUAAGAUAUGGGUCAAGUGACCUUGUUUUAUAAAGUCCGGAAGACUCACAGUGGGUUAGAUGCUACAGGCACAAGUAACAGAUACCCAUUCAGACUGGCCUAAACAAUAAGGAAAUCCAUUAAGAAAUGGCUCAAGACCAGGUGUGGUAGCGCACACCUAUCGUCCCAGCUACUCGGGAGGUUGAGUUGGGAGGAUCACUUUGAGUUUGAGGCUGCAGUGAGCCAUGAUUGCACCACUGCACCCCAGCCUUGGCAAUAGAGCAAGACCUUGUCAAAAAAAGAAAAGAAAUGGGGCCAGGCGCAGUGGCUCACGCCUGUAAUCCCAGCACUUUGAGAGGCCGAGGCAGGCGGAUCACCUGAGAUUGGGAGUUCAAGACCAGCCUGACCAACAUGGAGAAACCCCGUCUCUACUAAAAAUACAAAAAAAAUUAGCCGGGUAUGGUGGCGCAUGCCUGUAAUCUCAGCUACUUGGGAGGCUGAGGCAGGAGAAUCGCUUGACCCCAGGAGGUGGAGGUUGUGAUGAGCCAAGAUUGCACCAUUGCACUCCAGCCUGGGCAACAAGAGCGAAACUCGGUCUCAAAAAAAAAAAAAAAAAGAAGAGAAAAGAAAUGGUUCAAAGUCUAGGCCCUCUUCAGAGCUGGCUGAUUCAGCUUGCCAACAGUGACAUCAGGGUGAGGCUUCCUCUGUCCACAGCAUUAGCUGCGAAUAUCCUCAUGGUCACAAGAUGGCUGCCAGUGGCCGUCAGGGUGUGUGCUUCCUUGUUCACAUCCAGUGGAAGAGUGACAGCCUGCUCCCCUUAGCUCUCUGACACCAAUGAGAAGGUGCUAAGAACUUACUAGCAGGCCUUUCCUCAUGACCCAUUCAACAGGAUUGGGUCACGUGCCUAUUCCUGAACCACUAAUUGGGAAGGGAUGGGAUUACUCUUAGACCAGUGGUUCUCAACUGAGCAUGAGUUUGUCUUCCAGGUGACAGUUGGCCAUGUUUGGAGACAUUUAUGGUUGUCACAACUGGGGUGAUGCUACUGGCAUCUCAUGGGUAGAGGCCAGGGAUGCUGUCAAACAUCCUACAAUGCACAGGACAGCCUCACAACAAAGAAUUAUGGCCCUAAGUGCCAAGGUUGAGAAAGUCUGCCUUAGACCUGUCAGGGCUGCCCCCAGCCUGGGGUCUGUUUCCCCCAAAACACGCACAUCUCAGCGGACAGGGCCAGAAUGCACUUUGGGGGCCAGCCACAGCCCCUGCCAGCCUCCCAGUUCCCCCAGAUCCUACCCUGGGCUUCCCCUGUAAGAGCUUUAUAAUGAGAUUUCAAUUUUAUAAAAUUAUAAGGGGCCUCUUAGGAGUUUUUGCCUGACAUAUCUUUAUGAACCUACCCUGAGUGUUUGUCCCUGGAGAGCCAGGCCCAAGGAUACCAAUGGCUAGAACCAACAGAAAAGCACAGCUGCCGGCAGGAGGCCUCACCCUCCCGCAGUGUGAGGCAGAGCAGCACAGUGGCUCAGAACAACAGCAUGUGCUGGGUGACCUUUGGCAAGUUGAUUCACCUCUCUAAACCUCAGCCUUCUGAGCUGCUAAAUGGGGCUGUUGUGAUUGCUGGAUGAGGCGAGGCCUGCGAAGUGGCUGGCAUGCAGCAGGUGCUAAUGAGUGCUGCAAAGGUGAUGUCACGCAGGCAGCUUCCCGUGGCCAGAGAAACAUUGCAGAGAAGGGAUAAGUAGGGCUUAGUGACUUUGACGGGUCAAUGGAAGAAUGACCCAAAGAAGGCUUCAAGGCCAGGCCUGCAGUUCUCCACCACAAAGGCCCUCACUGAUAGCACCCACUCCCCCACACUCAGCUUUGGGGCCUAGGUCUGGUCACCCAGCUAGAAGCCACAGGACCCUGAGGCGUCCGAGGGUGGGAAGGCUGAGAGGCAGCUGAGACUCCUGGAGGCCGUGACUGGGAAGCCCUCUCUUUAGAAAGGCCAUCAGCUUCCUGCGUGGGGGUGACUGGCUCCUCCCGAGAGAUGGCAGCCAGGUCUGACUGUGCCCCUCUCUUACAGACCCCAUGAUGGAGCUGACAGGCACUGACCCUUCAGAGCUCGACGGCCAGCAGGAGAUGGAGGACUUCGAGGAGAACGCCUACAGCUAUGCGAGCGUGGACAGCAGCGCCGAGGCCAGUGUCCUCACUGAACAGGCCAUGAAAGAGAUGGCCUACUACAAUGUGCUAUAGCGCAAGCUGGGCCACCCCUAACGGGGGCCGGGGGCGAGGGCAUGGGGGUGAGACCCAUGGGCUGCAGGCUGCACCUCCUGCAGCCGAGAAACAAGCUACUGCCCCACUGUUCUGAGCCCUCCCUCCCCGAGUCAUUUGCACCACUAGGGACCUUUAGACCAAAUGGAGACUGUACUACUGGCCCCGGCUGUGAGCCAGCACAGGCCCAGGCAUCCCAGCAAGGGAAGGAGAACACGCGAGGCCCAGAUCUGGGUCUCCCUGGCCUGCUUCCGUGGGGAGUGGGAGAAGUGGGGCCACUGGGGACAGGUCACAAGGGCACCGGCCCUCGGGGUCUCUCCAGGCCCAGCAGAGCUCUUCAGGGGUCCUGACACUGGAAGAAGAGACCACUUGAGCCAUGUCUUUUUCACGGCCAACUCCUGCCUCUAAGGAUGUCUGAGCUCCCCUCUGGCCAGUACUGCCCACCUCUACCUUGUCCAGGCCCCCUUCCCCGCCCUGUCGACGGACCGCCAGGCAGGGCACUCUGCCUUCUACCUCCCGGGGUCUCCCAUGCGCUCCUCAAGCCAGGUGUGCACGUGGCCCUGGCCCUGGCCUGCAGGACAGCUGGGGGGCACCCAGCCCCCAGAAGACCCCUGUCCUACAUCCCUUUCUGGAAGUGAGUGUCCCUACAGUGGAUUGCAACACAUGUCGUCCACUUCGACCCUAGCUGGAGUGCCUCACCAGGGGGCCCCACUAGGAACAAAGCCAGGACAGGCCCCGCGUCAGGCACACACUAACAAAACCAGAAGCAUGGGGCAGGGCAGGGCGGAGUGAGGGCAUCACAGGGGACCAAGAAGGGCUGUCCUUGGGGGAGGCCCAGGACCACCUGUCGGGGAGGGGGACCGCAGUCAUUUCUCAUUCCUCAGUGUCCACCUUGCGACGGGGAUAGCCACGAGUCAGCAGCUUCCCGGAAAGAGCAACGUAUUUUAAAAAGGAAAGUAAAGCCCACAGAGGGAAAUCAAGGGUUUUUUUGAGCAAAGGGGGUCUUCUGAAGGUAACUUAUUAUUUUUUUCUUUCCAACUGUGUGUCACCUAUGACCUUUUCUGAUGGAGAUGCAUUUUCUUUUUCCAAGCGUAAGCUUCCUAAUGUGCUGUGCGUGCUUCCUACCCACCCACCCCGAGCAGCCUGGCCGGGCAGGACUGGGGCUCCAUGGGGACUGUCACCCUGGCCCUGGAGGUGCAGCCGCUGGCAGCAGCCUCAGCAGGCUGGGGUGGGAGGCAGGAGAAGGCAGAGCUGGGAAGCCCUCCACCCCUGCCUGGCUCCUGCAGUCGCUGACUUGCUCUGUCCCAUGUCCCAUCCUCGGCUGUCAGGGCUGCUGACUCUGCUCAGCCAACAGCUAGCUCCCUCGCUCGCCUGCUCUCUUCCCCUCUGUUCCCACGCCAGCUCCUGCCCCUGGAACCAGAGAUGACAGGCCCAGGGCAGUGAAAUAGCACAUUCAGGAACUCUAGGGCACCCGGACCCCCCCACCCACUUGCCUCCUGAGGCCUCAGUGGGGAGGGGCAAGCAGGGGUCUUCCCCAAAGGCACAGAUGAAGCCACUAGCUUCAGCCUAGAAACCCGGAGAAGGGAACAGCCUGCGGUGGGAGGAACCAAUCUGCAGCGCAGCCACCCCCAAGGCUGGAUCCUUAAGUGAAGGACCAAGCCAGGCCUCAGGGUGACUGUGAUCAGGACUGAGGGGUGGACAAGGUGGCCCAAGUAUGGCUUCCAGACCCCGAAGCCCCACGACCUCCCAGGUGCCCGCCAUGAUGACCCUCAGGUGGCAGUGACCCCGUCACUGUAUAAGACAUUUUCUCCUGCUGAGCAGAAGGCAUCAUCCCCUGCAACUACCUCUUCCCACGUCUUUCUCCCCUGGUACCAAAAAGAACCCUGUACCUCUCCUCCUCCUCCUCCCUCCUGCCAGUGCAGUGGCCUUGGUCUUGGAAACUGAAGGGAGAAGGUCUGGCCCCCAGGGUGGGGCUCUCCUUUCCCUCCCCCAGCCCCGCCGUCAGCACUGGCCCUCUGUGAGGUUCGAUACUUGAACGCCCCCUGCCCUGUGCCUUGGACCUGGGCAAAGCUAGGAGGAGGAAACAGCACAACUCACAGUUUGAGCUGGGGGGUGGUCUUGGCAAGGCUCCUGUCUGUACCCCUCCCUAACCUUCUCAAAAGAGGUGCACAGCCUCUCGGGUGACUUGGAAACUCCUGGACAAAUUCCAUUCUAACUUAUUUUGACAUGUAUACAAACCAACUGUUUAGAGAUUCCACUUGUGCAAAGCCCUACUGUGUUUUUAUGUUCCUGUUUAAAAGAGAAGUUUACUUAGCAAUAAUUAUAAAUAAAUGAAUAUUCUUUA